ACCCGGCUCGGCCACUGCUGGGCGGACACCUGGGCGCGCCGCCGCGGGAGGAGCCCGGACUCGGGCCGAGGCUGCCCAGGCAAUGCGUUCACUCGGCGCAAACAUGGCUGCGGCCCUGCGCGCCGCGGGCGUCCUGCUCCGCGAUCCGCGUUGUGACCACAGGAUGAGCUGAUGGGACUGUGGAUCUCACACACCUGGCUGGGACAGCAUUUCCAACUGUGACACCUUGAACAAGGCACCUAACCUCGCCAGAGCUUUGUGGCAUCCAGCAGCUGGAGGGUCUGUCAGCCAUGGAGGUGGAAGUCAGGUGCAGCUGCAGCGGCCGUCACCACAGAAACAGCCCAGCAUGCCCAGGGUGCAAAACCUCAAGUUCAACCGCAGAAGAGGAAGCCGAAAACUGGAAUAUUAAUGCUAAACAUGGGAGGCCCUGAAACUCUUGGAGAUGUUCACGACUUCCUUCUGAGACUCUUCUUGGACCGAGACCUCAUGACACUUCCUAUUCAGAAUAAGCUGGCACCAUUCAUCGCCAAACGCCGAACCCCCAAGAUUCAAGAGCAGUACCGCAGGAUUGGAGGCGGAUCCCCCAUCAAGAUAUGGACUUCCAAGCAGGGAGAGGGCAUGGUGAAGCUGCUGGAUGAAUUGUCCCCCAACACAGCCCCUCACAAAUACUAUAUUGGAUUUCGGUACGUCCAUCCUUUAACAGAAGAAGCAAUUGAAGAGAUGGAGAGAGAUGGCCUAGAAAGGGCUAUUGCUUUCACACAGUAUCCACAGUACAGCUGCUCCACCACAGGCAGCAGCUUAAAUGCCAUUUACAGAUACUAUAAUCAAGUGGGACGGAAGCCCACGAUGAAGUGGAGCACUAUUGACAGGUGGCCCACACAUCACCUCCUCAUCCAGUGCUUUGCAGAUCAUAUUCUAAAGGAACUGGACCAUUUUCCACUUGAGAAGAGAAGCGAGGUGGUCAUUCUGUUUUCUGCUCACUCACUGCCCAUGUCUGUGGUCAACAGAGGCGACCCAUAUCCUCAGGAGGUAAGCGCCACUGUCCAAAAAGUCAUGGAAAGGCUGGAGUACUGCAACCCCUACCGACUGGUGUGGCAAUCCAAGGUUGGUCCAAUGCCCUGGUUGGGUCCUCAAACAGACGAAUCUAUCAAAGGGCUUUGUGAGAGGGGGAGGAAGAAUAUCCUCUUGGUUCCGAUAGCAUUUACCAGUGACCAUAUUGAAACGCUGUAUGAGCUGGACAUCGAGUACUCUCAAGUUUUAGCCAAGGAGUGUGGAGUUGAAAACAUCAGAAGAGCUGAGUCUCUUAAUGGAAAUCCAUUGUUCUCUAAGGCCCUGGCCGACUUGGUGCAUUCACACAUCCAGUCAAACGAGCUGUGUUCCAAGCAGCUGACCCUGAGCUGUCCGCUCUGUGUCAAUCCUGUCUGCAGGGAGACUAAAUCCUUCUUCACCAGCCAGCAGCUGUGACCCCCGCCGGUGGACCCCGUGGCGUUAGGCAAAUGCCCAACCUCCAGAUACCUCCGAUGUGGAGAGGGUGUUAUUUAGAGAUCAAGGAAGGAAGUCAUCCUUCCUUGAUAUAUAUACAGCCUUUGGGUACAAAUUGUGUGGUUUCUUGAGGAUUGGACUCUUGAUGGAUUUCUAUUUUUAUAUAACUAUACAGUAAGCAUUUGUAUUUUCUCUCUCUAGGUAUAAGUUACUAGUUUGGAAUGUCCAUCAGGACCUUUAAUAAAUGAGUUAAAAAUUUGUCUUAUGAGACACACCUAUUUAAGUACAGAUUUUGGCUUUAUUGCCCAAAACCCUCCUGAAAGGGUACGGAGAGUCCCCUCUGUGGGCUGGCAGUGUGAAUGAGAUCUGUUUAGUCUCGUGCAUAUAGUUGCUGUUUUUUAAAUGAACACAGUUGAGUAUUUGAAGUGAAUUUGAAAAAGAAAUGUUACUUAAUCUUUCCCUAAGCCCAUGGGUUACAGAAUGCUAGGGAGGCAAUUUGGUUACCUGCAAUGGCUGCUUUUGCCAGCGAGGCCACCAUUCAUUGGUCAUCUUGGUAUUUGUGUGUGAAUCUCACUUUCCUCAAUGUAAAAAGGAAUCAAGUAUGGAUUUCAGAGGUGCUCUUAGAUUCCCCAUACACCCAAGGGUAAUAAACGUGUACAAGUACAGUGUUCAUGAUACGUGCCUUGGUGGGAGUCCGUGGUGCCACAGGGAAGGGGCUCCCACUGCUUCUGGUCUCCAGGGACAGUGCUGCUGGAAAGGCUAGUGAUGAGCUUCACCCUGGAGCUCCUCCCGGGACCUUGCAAGCCUCUCCAUCCAGCAUCUUCUCUAUCUUAGUUGAAUGCCUUCUUUCUGAACAUUUGUUUUAAGAAUUAUUUUAUAAAGUCAACAAUACUUUGCUUGAAUUCUUUCUUAAUUUACGAUUUUUUAUUAUAAAAAUGUAUAGUGAUACAAUGGGACAUGUGAAGAAUACAGAAAAGUAACCACUUUAAUGCAAUAACUGUUAUCAUAAUAUUGUAUUUCGUGGUAGUCCUUUCCUGUAGAUAUUUUUAAUGCCAUUUAAUGCCAUUGUCACCUUGGAUUUAUGAGUGAAAAGUGUUUCUAAAAAUAUAGAAAUAAUGUCAGAUCAGAGUCUGAUCUUCUAUGUUUGUAUUUAAAUGGAUUAAAAGAUCCCCGGUGGUUCCAUGAAGAAUUUGUAAAGAUCACUUUCUCUUUCCUCCAAGCCCUGAAACUUUGUUCUUCAAAAGAGCGUUUCUUUUUUUUUUUUUUUUUAGCCAGUUUAUAAAGUGGAAGUAUUAGGAGAUUCAUAAAUCUUCUAUAUUGAGAAUUGGCUAUGUUAAUAAAUAUUACAACAUCAUUAAGGUUUUAGCUAAGUUUGAUUCAUGCUGUCUGUUAAAUCAAAACUGAUCUAAAUCAGAAUUAUUAAAUGUGAGGAGCUUUUUUAAUACAGGAAAAGAAACAUGUCAUCCACUUGAGUUAAUAGUUUUCCUACGUUGAUGACAGCCCUCAUGAGUAGCAUCCACAUUUUUAAAAUUUCAAAUUGGUUUUUCUACUAGUAGAUUGUGUUUCUAGAGAAAGAUACAAGGCAUAGGUGAUUGUUUAGGAUUUUCCUCUAGCCUUUGCCAUUACCUUUUUGGGGAUGAGGUUCACAGUAGACUUUGAGUGACCGUCCCACCGUGAAGUGAAUUCUCUGAGCUGGUGGUGUGGUGCUGGAAGGAAGGUUAUUUUUGGAGCCACUCUCUCCCCUUAAGGAUAUUUCCCAAGGGCCUGCUUCAAUUCUUUGAUGACUUUAGAGGUGAAAAAAUAUUUUUAUGGAGAUGAUGCAGAAAACUCCAAUUCAGGAGCCCUUGCGAGUAUAUCUGAAGCACUUAUUUGCUAAGGAAACCUGAAUUGAUAGCAGUACUGUGCUGUCUGGAAUAAUGUCCUUGAUACUGAGUUGGGACCAGACUGGCUUUUAUAGUGACAGGCAAAGAGGAAUUUAUUGAGAUCACUGCUCAUGGCAUUUGUUGCUGUAAGAAGUGUUGCCUUUGAUUGUUACUAACCACGGAUGGGUAACGGUCAUACAUUAGGCUAGUGUUUGGUAGGACAAAAUCUUUUUAGAGCUUUGAGAAUUGUCAUCCUGUUGGUCAACUUUGAAAUACAAAUGUUUGCCCUGGUAAUUAGCAAUGAACUGCUGGCAGUUUCUUCAGCUGUGUAUAUACGGAUCUGGCUUUUAAUUGAUGAAUCAACUUCUACAGAAACUUUUGCAGGGACAGUGUUGAUGAGGCAGUUUAGCUUGCCAGGGUGAUGAUAAAGCCCAGGUCCCUGCAUGUAUAGUGCUCUUCUAAAGAAUAUGCAUUCUUGAACUACUUAACUUUUUAAAAAUCACAAUAAAUUUUUGCACUCAAAAUUUGCUUCGUAUCAGGAGAAAUGAACUCAUUGUUUUGUUUUGUUUUUUUUUUUUUUUAAGAUGGAGUCUUGCUAUGUCACCCAGGCUGGAGGGCAGUGGUGCGAUCUCGGCUCACUGCUACUUCCACCUCCUGGGCUCAAGUGAUCCUCCCACCUCAGCCUCCAAGUAGCUGGGACUACAGGAGUGCUUCACCACGCUGGGCUACUUUUUUAUAUUUUUUGUAGAGAUGGGGUUUUGCCAUGUUGUCCAGGCUGGUCUUGAACUCCUGGGCUCAAGGGAUUCUCCUGCCUCAGUCUCCCAAAGUGCUGGGAUUACAAGGAUGAGCCUCUGCACCUGGCCCUGAACUCAUUAUUAAAAGCCCUUUAAAUGUGAGGCUGGGUGCCGUGCCUUACAUGUGUAAUUCCAAUACUUUGGAAGGCCAAGGUUGGAGGAUUGCUUGAUCCCAAGAGUUCAAGACCAGCCUGGGCAACAUAGGGAGACCCUGACUCUACAAAAAAUAAAGUAAAAAUUAACUGGGUGUAGUGUCACAUGCCUGUAGUUCCAGCUACUUAGGAGGCUGAGGUGGUAGGAUUGCUUGAGCCCAGCAGUUUGAGGUUGCAGUGAGGUGUGAUUGCACCACUGCACUCCAGCCUGGGUGACAGAGGAAGACCCUGUCCCAAAACCAAAAAAAAGAAAAGAAAUACAGAGACUGGGUCAUUUACAAAGGAAAGAGGUUUAAUUGACUCGGUUCGGCUUUCUGAGGAAGCCUUAGGAAAUUGACAAUCAUGGCAGAAGGGGAAGCAGAUGUCUUACAUGGCAGUGAGUGAGAGCAAGCAAAGGGGAAGAGCCCCCUUAUAAAACCAUCAGAUCUCGUGAGAACUGGCUGUCACAAGAACAGCAUGGGGGAACUGUCUCCAUGUUCCAAUCUCCUUCCACCAGGUCCCUCCCUCAACACGUGGGGAUUAUGGGGAUUACAAUUUGAAAUGAGAUUUGGGUGGGGAACAGAGCCAAAUCAUAUCAUUCCACCCUGGCCCCUCCCAAAUCACAUGUCCUUUUUACAUUUCAAAACCAAUCAUGCCUUCACAACAGUCCUCCAGAGUCUUAACUCAUUCCAGCAUUAACCCAAAAGUCCAAGUUCAAAGUCUCAUCCAAGACAAGGCAAGUCCCUUCUGCCUGUGAGCCUGUAACAUUAAAAGCAAGUUAGUGACUUCCAAGAUACAAUGGGAGUACAGACAUUGGUAAAUGUUCCCAUUCCAAAUGGGAGAAAUUGGCCAAAACACAGGGGCUACAGGCCCCAUGCACCACUGCACUCCACUGUGCAAGUCUGAAACCCGGCAGGGCACUCCUUAAAUUUUUUUUUUUUUUUUUUGAGAUGGAGUCUCGCUCUGUUGCCCAAGCUGGAGUACAGUGGCACGAUCUCGGCUCACUGCAACCUCCGCCUCUUGGGUUCAAAGGAUCAUCCUGCCUCAGCCUCCGGAGUAGCUGGGCUACUCAGGCGUGUGCCACCAUGCCCGGCUAAUUUUUGUAUUUUUAGUAGAGAUGGGGCCUGACCAUGUUGGUCAGGCUGGUCUCUAAUUCCUGACCUCGUGAUCCACCCGCCUCAGCCUCUGAAAGUGUUGGGAUUACAGGCGUGAGCCACCAUCCCCGGCCUACUCAAUAAAUCUUAAAGUUCCGGAAUAAUCUCCUUUGACUCCAUGUCUCACCUCCAGGUCACGCUGAUGCAAGAGGUGGGCUAAUCUUUCUAGUAAAUUCCAUAUUUAAUUCAAGAAACCAUAACUUAAGGCAUGUAAAAGAGAUCCUUUGCUCAAUGUGAUGCCAUUGUGCUUAUCCAAAGUAUAUUAUUAUUACCCACAAAGGGUGAGAGAUUAGGCUGCAGCCAUACCCCAAGUGGAGUGAGCAGCAAGACCUGCCCCCUGCUCAGAGUGUAGAUGACUGGGGGCACCUGCAUUCCUAGGGGCUCUGCCGUAUGAGCUCCUGUCGAUGCGGCAAAGGACCACCUUGCCCAACGACAGCGGGAAGGCAGAAUUUAAAGCUGGCAGCUGUAAGCGAACGUCUAUGUGUGCGCACGGGGGCACGUGAAGGCACAGGUGCAUCAGCCAAGAACCUCCAAUUCACCUCUUAACCUUCUCACCUCACCUGAAACCCCUUCUGCCAGAAUCCUGAAGGUGGCCCAGGAACAGGGCUCCUAACGUUAGGUGGAAAUGGGAAAUUCAUUGAGAUGUCACAAGCUGGAAUAAGAAAAUUCUGAGCUCACCCGGAAACUAAUGCCCUAAAUUAAGAUUAUUCAGCUUCUCAAUUUUUAAUAGCAAAAUGGAGACCUGAGUGUGGAUAACUUUUAGUAUCUGUGGGGGAUCCUGGAACCAAUUCCCUGCCAAUAUAGAAGGACAACUGUCUACAGUACUUGAAGUAUUAUUAACUACAUUCGCCAUGCUGUAUGUUAGAUCCCCAGAACAUAUUUAUCCUGCAUAUCUAAAAUUUUGAUCAUUUUACAAACUUUCUAUUUUUUUUGUCAAUUUUCUCCAGCUAGACACUUGUGCAAUACGGCUAUUAUCUGAUCUUUGCCUUAAAUGUUGUGCUUCUUUUCCAUAUGCACGUAUUUUGCAAAAUAUAAAGUGUGUAGAGCUAUAUAGCACUCAGCCAAGUGGUGGGUACCUGCAGGUGCUUCAGAGAAGUAAAUUGAUGCUGCUAAUAUUUGUUGAAUGGCACGAAUAUGAUGAGCAAUAGCAGGUGGUGCCCUUCAGCCAGACCAUCGCUCCGUGCGUCUGAUGCAUCUUGCCAAAGAGUAGUUCUGGGAGGUGGUUGCCUCUAGAGAACACAUUCCUCCUAUUCUGGGGUCCCGUGAGAGAAAGAAAUGCUUUUGCUUUUGAUGUGGGACUCUUACUAAGCCUUUCUUCAGAGAAAAGGAAGUGAAAAAUGCACCCCAUGAUAAUCAGUUUCUUACAACAUACUGUGAUAGUACCGGCUUCGUUGUUUUUAGCUGGAAUCAUUAGCUUCCAUUUUUAGAAUAACAGCUAUUGGCUAAAUUAGGCUACAGUAGGCCAUUAAGAUGGAUGUUGGAAUUAAAAACAUUUUUGGAAAAAAGCCUGCUUUGAGCCUUUGUUAUAAGCCCUUGGGUAGAGAUCUGGGUCCUGUUUCUGAUUUCUUGUGAGCCUUCACUCUGACAGUUUUGUUUCCAGAAACACACUCUUAGCCUGCUCCUGAAAUGGGAACAGACAGGCCAACUUCCCCUCUCCAGUCUCCCCUGCGGGUCAAAGCUUUACUUUCCUGUCAUGUUAAGAAAGAAUAGAUUUAACCUUGAUAAUCCAUGUAGUAUUCUGUAUUUUUACCUUUUCCUUAUCUGAAAAAAAGUGUAUAUAUGGCAUGGAAUUGAUUGCACAGGCACAUGGCAUGUUGGCUUGUGAACCAAUUGUUAAAAUUUCAAGUUAAUCAUUAAAAUAAUAUCUUUCAAAUUAAGUUAUAUUAAAAACAAAGGUAACAUUCUAAAUUCAUUACUUUCUAAUUAUUUCGCCCUUUUUUUUGUCGUUGAUUAUUUAGACUUAAGAAAGUGAUGGGAAAAACGUUAAUAACACAGUACAUAAGUUGUUUCUGUAGCCAUUACACUGUGAUUUUCACAAACACUUGAACACUUGAAUAGUCUUCCAUUAUUUGAAAACUAUUAUUCAACUUAUCCAAGUGAAGUAUUGGCAUACAAAGAAGUUGUUUCAUAUUUGCAUUGCUCAUGAAUGUAAACAAAAUGUCGAUAUGUGUGAACUAUACUUGUUGAUCAAUUGCAACCAUAGGUUGGCUGCAGAUGCGAGAGCUUGGUAAACAUCAACAAAAGCAUUCUCUGAGAAUGAAUUGACUAUAUGGAAUUUGUAGGAAAGUGUAUUGUGUAUUUUAUUAUUAUUUGUAAAUUGUGUAUUCCACAUCUUUUAGAUUAGUAAAAUUUAUAGUAAACAUACUCUCACACCUA